ACACGAAACCUGCACUGGCUGGGGAACUGCAGACUGAUCGCCAGCGGCACGUGCGGGGCGCCGACGCCUCGCCGCAGGGUGCGGGUGCCCGCGGAGCCAGCCAGCCAGAGAACCAGCAGGAGAGGAAAAAGGGUGGGCGCGCGGGUGGGCCCGGGAGGCGGAGACCUUCGGGAAGCUGGGGCCACGCGGCGGUGCAGGCGACGGGACUGCAGUGCCACCUCUCCCGAGAAACCCACACGCUCGCACGCCCGCGCGCGCACGCACGUGCACACGGUGGGCAGGGAGAAAACGAGAGAGUCUGAGUGCUGGGCGCGUUUUAGCGAUGGCUUCUGCUCUCAACAGCAAAAUUAACCCGCCCGGCACUUGCCAGGGCUCCAAAGCCGACGGUGGCGCCGGCUGGAGAAUGGACUGUGAUCCCCAGAUGCACGUGAAAAUGUGCAAGAAGAUCGCCCAGCUCACCAAGGUGAUUUAUGCCCUGAACACCCGCCAGGAUGAGGCUGAGGCCAGCAUGGAGGCGCUGCGGGAAGCGCACCAGGAGGAGCUCCAGAAUGCGGUGGCAGAGACCAAGGCCAGGCUCCUGCAGGAACAGGGCUGCGCAGAGGAGGAAGCCCUUCUACAGCGCAUCCAGGCCCUGGAGAGCGCCCUGGAGCUGCAAAAGAGGCUGACGGAGGAGGCGCUGGCUGAGUCGGCCUCGUGCAGGCUGGAGACGAAGGAGAGAGAGCUGAGGGUGGAGGCAGAGCACGCCGAGCGAGUCCUCACGCUCUCCAGGGAAAUGCUGGAGCUCAAGGCUGACUACGAGAGGAGGCUCCAGCACCUGACGAGCCACGAGGCUACCCCGCAGGGCCGGCUGCCCCAGGAGAGCCCUGAAACCAAGUCGGAGCCAGGCCAGGGCCCGGAGAUGCAGGAGGUCCUGCUAGAGGUGCAGCGGCUGCGAGUGGAGAACCAGCAGCUGAGCAAGGACUACGCCCGCAAGGCCGAGGAGCUGCAGGCCACCUACGAGAGGGAAAACGAGGCCAUCCGGCAGGCCAUGCAGCAGUCGGUGAGCCAGGCCCUGUGGCAGUGGCAGGAGAAGGAGUCGGACCUCCGCAAGAACUUCCAGGUCCAGGAGUCAGCCCUGCAGGCUCAGGUCCGGAAGCUGGAAGGAGACCUGGAGCACAGAGGCCGCAAGAUAAGUGACCUGAAGAAGUACGCCCAGAAGCUGAAGGAGAGGAUUCAGGACCUGGAUGUGCAGCUUAAGGAGGCUCGACAGGAGAAUUCAGAGUUGAAAGGCACUGCAAAAAAACUUGGGGAGAAGCUGGCUGUUGCCAAAGACAGAAUGAUGCUGCAGGAGUGUCGUGGGACACAGCAGACAGAUGCCAUGAAGACUGAGUUAGUUUCAGAGAACAAAGUCCUGCGGGAAGAGAAUGACUUGGAAGCCGGCAAUCUUCAUCCUCAGCAGGAUCAAAGCUGUCUCAAGGAGUGCCCUUGCAUGAAAGGAGGCACAGAUAUGCAGACCAAGAAAGAGGCAAGUGCUGAGACAGAAUAUAUGAAGCAACAAUAUGAAGAAGACCUUCGUAAAAUCAAACAUCAGACAGAAGAGGAGAAGAAACAUCUCAAAGACCAGCUAGUGAAGCGACUAGAAGACUUGGUAAAGAAGCACACCGUGGAAAUCAAAUCCGUUCGCUCGUCCGUGGAGGCUGAAAGAAAGAAACUGCAGAGGGAAGUAGAAGCACAGUUGGAGGAAGUGAGGAAGAAAUCAGAAAAGGAGAUAAAGCAGCUGGAAGAAGAGAAAGCAGCCCUCAAUGUGAAGCUUCAGAAUUCUCUGCUUGAGGUUUUAAGGCUGGAAGAAUUUAUCCAACAAAAUAAGACACGCCCCACAGGAGCUGAGGAAAGUCCCCAGGAAUUAGGCCGCCAGCACUGCAGCAUUCUGGAGACCCAGGAUCCAUGCUUGAAGCUGGAUGAAACUUCGCCGAGAGGAGAGGAGUAUCAAGAUAAGUUAGCAGCUGAAGAAGGAACCAGCAGUGAUGAAGAAGAAAGGACCAAAGUGCUUCUCAAGGAGGGAAGUGACCCACAACCUCCACUGGGCUCUUUGUUGAAGGAGAAAACAUCCAAAAUCCAGCGUCUAGAGGAGGACUGGCAAAGCCAGAAGGCCAAAUUGCAAGCCCAGGUCUCACAGAUGCAGCAGGCUCUGGAGCAGUGCACCAGCAACUACAGGGAGGACCUGCAGGCACUCAAGCAGCUCUCGGACCUGGAGAGGGAGAAGCUGCAGCGUGAGCUCCAGGAGACCACUCAGCAGAACCACGCCAUGAAAGCCCAGCUCGAGGCUUCCCACCAGAGAGCCCUGCGCAUGCUGGAGAAGGCCAGACAUCAGGAACUCAAGGCCACAGAGGAACGCUUGAAGAAGGAAUCCAGCCACAGCCUCCAGAUCCAACACCAGACACACCGACUGGAGCUCCAGGCCUUGGAGGAAAAGGCCAGGCAAGAGCUGCAGGAGGAGCGUGAGAGGAUGCAGGCACAGCAGGCCCUGCUGCUAGAGUCGCUCAGACAGGAGCUGUCGGAGCAGCAAGCUGCCUGUUCUGGGCACCAGAAGGACUUGGAGGCACUGCAGGCCGAGCUGAGGGCUCUGGGCAGACAGCAAGCCAGCAGCCAGUGUCCAGGAGACAGCAAGGAUCACAUAAUCGCCACAGAGGAGCGGGGCGGCCCGGGCCAGGCCGGCUCCCCACCGGGCGCUGCUGGGCAGGGUUCCGGCGAGGGAUGCGGGCUCUGGGAGGAGAACGCGCAGCUCCAGGACGCGGUGCGGCGGCUGCGCGCGGAGGUGGAGCAGCAUCAGCAGGAGGCGCAGAAGCUCCGAGACCAGCGCAGGUUCCUGGAGGAGACUCAGCAAGCCCAGCGGGCCAGGGAGGUGGAGACACUGCGCCAGGAACACCGGAAGGAGAUGCAGGCCAUGGUGGCAGAUUUCAGUAGUGCCCAGGCCCAGCUCCAGGCCCGGCUGGCUGCCCUGGAAGCCGAACUGAAAGAUUCCGGAGAGAAGCCAGGGAAGGGAGCGUCCAGGCCCGAGGACCUUCAGCUCAUUGGCCGCCUGCAGACCCGCCUGAAGGAGAGAGAGGACAUCAUCAAGCAGCUCACGGAAGAGAGAAGAUUUCACUACGCAGCAUUCCCCAGUGCCAUGUCCCACCGGAAUCGGUCUUUCUCUUUCAAUCCUCACCCGGGAUAUUUGACCCCUUCCAUGAAGAAAAAGAAGGUGGAGGACGUGCCCAGCCGCGUGGUCAGCGUGCCGAACCUCGCCUCCUAUGCAAAGAACUUUCUGAGUGGCGAUCUGAGUUCCAGGAUUAAUGCCCCUCCAAUAACUACAUCACCCAGCUUGGACCCAAGCCCCAGCUGUGGCCGGACCUACAAACCCAACCAGUCUACAGAUGCAAAAACUGCCACAAGGACCCCAGAUGGUGAAACGGCCCAAGCCAAAGAAGUCCAGCAGAAACAGGGCUCUCCGCACCAGGAAUGGUUCACCAAGUACUUUUCUUUCUAAGCUAACCUUUGGGAUACAUCACAGAGGAUACUUGAAAAACAUUUAUUUUAAAUCAUCCGAUUGAAGGAAUGAACUAACACCAACCAACCAAAUAAUAUGCUUAUGAUUUAUAUAUGAUAGCUAAAACAAAUUUUGGCGUUAACACUUCAUACUGUUCUGCCAGGCACAGCAGCUCACGCCUGUAAUCCCAUCACUUUGGGAGGCUGAGGCAGAUGGACUGCUUGAGUCCAGGAAUUUGAGACCAGCCUGGCCAAUAUGGUGAAACCCCAUCUCUACAAAAUAUACAAAAAUUAGCCAGGCAUGGUGGCGUGUGCCUGUGGUCCCAGGUACUUGGGGGACUGAGGCGGGAGGAUCACUUGAACCUAGGAGGCAGAGGUUGCAGUGAGCCAAGUUCGAACUCCUGCAUUCCAACCAGCCUGGGUGACAGAGGGAGACCCUGUCUCCAAAAAAAAAAAAAAAAAAAAAAAAAAAAAAAAAAAAAAAAAAAAUUGACAUUAAACCAGUGUUAUUAAAAGUCAUCUAUAGGAAAAUGUUAUUAGCGUUACUAAUGACCCAUACCUUGUAUUUCUAGUGUCCAUAACAUCAUACUCCAUUUUGUGGAACAUCAGACUUUGUGAUUUCCAUGAUCUAUUUCAAAAGUGGUUGUACUUGUCCUUAGGAUGCUAGUCAACUCCACUGGAAAGCUGUUUCUAUGUAAAAUGAUGCAAUUCCAAAAUGCACAUCUAACCUCAAUAGGAAGACAAAUAACAGUUAAACAGGAAAGCCAACUAAAAACAAACCAAACCUACCAGAAAUGGAUGGUAGCAUGCUUGGACUGAAUACUUUCACUUCCUUGGUCUAAGACAAGCAGCAGAUUAUAGAUGGGAUAACACCCACCUCUAAAAGGGCUUUGCAAGGAUUAAGCAAGAUAACAUAAAUUAACAUGAAUUGGAAUUAAGUACCACAAGGUUUUUCUGUAAAUAACCAAUCCUAGCCCAGUUAUAGGUCUCAGUGUAAUGACCAUAGUGCCAACAUGAUCACUUGUGAAGGUCUCUAGAUUAUCUGUUCUUUGAAGUCAAAGAUCUUCUAGACUGGGCACAUGGCUCAUGCCUGUAAUCCCAACACUUUGGGAGGCUGAGAUGGGAGGAGAGCUUGAGGCCAGGAAUUUGAGACCAGCCUGGGCAACACAGCGAGACCUCCAUCUCUACAAAAAAAUAAUUAGCCCAAAGAAAACCCAGCUACUUGGAAGUCUGAGGUAGGACAGCAUGAGCCCAAGAGUUCGAGACCAGCCUGGGCAAGAUAGUGAGAUCCCAUCUCUACAGAUUAAAAAAAUAUAUAUAUAUAUCCCCUGAACCUCUGGUCUUUGGGUUUGAGCCAUUUGCCUCAUGGUGUGUUGCUUCUUCACUGCAUGAAUUCCCAGUGGGUUAAAGGAACCGCAAUGGCUGUUCACGGUGCUGACCUUGCUCUCAGUCCACACUGAUUUGUCUUACCUUCUGACAGAGCAAUGUGAUUUGACAAGACUCAAUAACAACUUUUAGGGGGCAAAAUAUUUUUUCAGUCUUUGGUGCUGGCCCAGAAGGUGGCCCACAAACCAAUGUUAAUUCUAUGCAUUGUCAAAUCUUUGCUCUUUGAAUAAAACUUUGAAUAACUGGGCAAUAAAAAUGGUUGACUUGUAUUGAUUUUCCACAGAAAGGUAAAAUUAGAUGAAGACAGCUUAGAAAUAGAAAGUUCAGUUCACAUUAACCUCAAUCACACCAUCUUAAAAAAAAAAAAGCUGAUUACAUAUAACUGUCAAACUUACGUAUUAAAGGUAAAUUUACUGCCUAAUCAAAACGAGGCUCCAAUGCAUUUUUAAAUGCAAACAAACACUUGUCACCAUACAUUAACACACCAUACUGUUUUUCACUACCAAAUAUUUUUUGUGAGUUUCCCGCUUAGAGUGUCUUAGUUCGUUCAGGCUGCUCUAACAAAAUAUCUUACUUAUACUGGAUAAUUUAUAAACAAUAGAAAUAUGUCACUCACAGUCCUAGAGGCUAAGUCCAAGAUCAAGGCACCAGCAGAUAUGGAGUCUGGGGAGGGCCCAUUCUUCAGAAAUGGGUGCCUGCUACGUGUCCUUACAUGGUGGAAGAGGCAAGAGCGCCUCCCUGAGCCUCUUUUGUAAGGGUACUUAUCCUACUCAUGAGGGUGAAGCCCUCAUGACUCCAUUGCUUCCCAAAAGCCCCACCUCUUAAUACUAUUACAUUGACAUUAGGUUCCAACAUAUGAAUUUUGGAAGGGACAUCAACAUUCAGGACAUAGCAGUGAACCCUGUAGGACUGCUCUUUAUUUUGUGCUUUCAAAAAGACUACAUACAGGUGGUUCUAUUUUUGUGUGUUGAAACACUUUCCCAGGCUGCACUUUGCAUUUCUGUCCUUAAACUCAGCAUGAUCCCUGGGCAAGGAGAAAAUUUUACUAGUUGAGAUCGUACAUAGGUUUUGACUCCUUUCUUGCUGCAGGUGACUGAAAAGAUCUUUCAGUCUUAAAUUUCUAAAUUCUACCCUGCAAUGAUUAUAUCUUUGUUAACAAAAUCUUUGCAUGCUUCCAUAAUUUUUUAUUGAGGCCAUAUGCCUUGGGUAUUGAAGUAAGGCAUUUAAGGACACAAACUUAAGCUUUUUGUUUGUUAUUACCAAACUGCCAUUCAGAAAGUUUCUAACAAUUUACACCCUUACCAGCAGUAAAUGAACCUACUGUGCCCUAACACUAUUGACAAAGAAAUACAAUUUGAUAGAUAAAACAUUCUAUUUUAGUUUGCAUAAUGAUUCCAUCAAUCUCUCAACAGCAGAGCGGUCUAGAGAUGACAGUGAUGGCGUAGAGGUGACAGUGAAGAUGAAGAGAAAUUAUCCAAUUCGGGAUUAAGUUAAGAGAGAGAAAAAAACAGUAUUUAAUGGUAAAUCUCUUCAGGCUGUAUUAUGACAGGGGUGGAAGAGUUAAUAUGUUCCUGCAGCAAAACUGAAAGGAAUACUAUCUGUUCCACAUGAAAGCAAACUGUUUUGUAAUUGGGGUAGGUAAAAAUGGAUUCACCCAGUCAAUGGCUGCACACCACAUACCUGAGCCCUUAACUGCUCUAACACUGAUGUAAUAUCCAACCCAACAUUUGUGAUUGAGGCUACUUGGUUAAUUUUUCUCCAGGAUCCAUCUGGAUUCUGCAGAUGAGGCUGGCAAAUUAAAUGGAACUAUGAUAGGGACCAUCUUACUGUAUCUGUCAGAU